AAGCGGAGAGCAGCUGUUGCAGUAACCUGUUGCAGAAAAGUGAAAGUAUAUCCGCAACAGUUGGCUCUGAUUGCAGAGAGCGCGCUUGUGAGAACUGAUGGCGGGUACGCGCAGAAAAUCUUUGCAAAACAGGCAAGUGGGAUCUCUUCUCAUUUUUCUGUGCAUAUCUGUGGGGGAUGCGACAACUAUCCGCUAUUCAGUGGCAGAGGAAAUGGAGAGCGGCUCGUUUGUGGCCAACGUAGCUAAGGACCUAGGACUGGAGGUAGGGAAGCUGGCUGCGCGCGGGGCGCGGCUGGUUUCCGAGGGCAACAAAAUGCAUUUCCGGCUCCACCGCAAGACGGGAGAUUUGUUUGUGAAGGAGAAACUGGAUCGGGAGUCACUUUGUGGCAAAGCCGACCCUUGUGUUCUGCACUUUGAAGUAGUCCUGGUGGAGCCGCUGCAGUCCUUCCGGGCCGAGGUCAGGGUAUUUGAUAUCAAUGACAAUGCCCCAGUUUUCCUAAACAAGGAGCCGCUUUUAAAGAUUCCGGAGAGCACCCCUUUGGGUUCACGUUUUCCUCUGCAGAGCGCCCAGGAUCUGGACGUGGGCCUUAACGGUCUCCAGAACUACACCCUGAGUGCCAAUGGGUAUUUCCACCUGCACACCCGCUUCUGCAGCCACGGGCCUAAAUAUGCUGAGCUGGUGCUGAACAAACCCCUGGACCGAGAGGAGCAGCCUGAAGUCAACUUGACAAUUACGGCGGUGGACGGCGGGUCCCCGCCUAAGUCUGGCACAGCUCACAUCCACGUGGUGGUUCUGGAUGUCAACGACCACGUGCCCCAGUUCUCGCGACUGGUGUACAGAGCCCAGGUAUCAGAGAACAGCCCCAAUGGCUCUUUGGUGGCCACGGUGACUGCCGUGGACCUAGACGAGGGCACCAACAAAGCGAUAACUUACUCUUUAGCUCAAAACCCAGAAGCAAUUCUCAAGACGUUUCAGAUUGACCCUCAAAAUGGAGAAGUUCGACUAAGAGGACCCCUCGAUUUUGAAGCCAUUGAAACAUACGACAUUGACAUUCAAGCUACAGAUGGUGGAGGCCUCUCUGCCCACAGCAAAGUCCUGGUAGAAGUGGUGGAUGUGAAUGACAAUCCUCCCGAAGUGAUGGUCUCCUCUGUGUCCAGCCCACUCCCUGAAGACUCACCACCACAGACAGUAGUAGCCCUUUUCACUAUCAGAGACCGGGACAUUCGAGUGGGAGGAAAAGUCACCUGCUUCCUCAGAGAAGACCUUCCCUUUGUAAUCAAACCUACAUUUGGGAAUUCUUACUCACUGGUCACUGACAGAAGCUUGGAUCGGGAGGAGGUCUCAGGCUAUAAUAUCACCAUUGUUGCCAUGGAUACUGGACCACCUAGCUUGUCUGCCGAGACUAUGAUAGAGGUGCUAAUAUCCGACGUUAAUGACAAUCCUCCAAUAUUUCGGGAAGAUUCCUAUAUCUUGACUGUUCGAGAAAACAACAGUCCUGCGGUUUUUAUUGGCAAAGUCCAUGCUGAGGAUCUUGAUUUGGGUGAGAAUGCCCAAAUAACAUAUUCUCUGUUGCCUCCAAAAAACGGAGAUCUUUCAGUCUUUGCUUACAUAUCCAUAAAUUCAGGCAAUGGGAAGCUCUACGCGCUGAGAACCAUGGAUUAUGAGGCCAUUCAAGAUUUUCAAUUUGUGGUAAAGGCAACUGAUGGGGGCUUCCUGUCACUGAGUAGCCAAGUUACUGUCAGAGUGGUUGUCCUAGAUGACAAUGACAAUCGUCCAAUGAUCUUAUACCCACUGCAGAACGGCACCUUGCCCUGCAAUGACCUGGUGCCCAGGUCUGCAGAGGCAGGCUACCUAGUGACCAAAGUGGUGGCUGUGGAUGGUGACUCAGGUCAGAAUUCUUGGCUUUCAUAUCAUCUACUUAAGGCCACUGACCUUGGGUUAUUUUCUGUUCAAAGACAAAAUGGAGAAAUCCAUACAUUAAGGCAGAUAUCUGAGAGAGACCCCAUGAUGCAGAAAUUGAUCAUUCUUGUUCAGGAUCACGGCCAACCAGCUCUUUCCACUACUGUCUCACUCAACAUCCUGCUGGUAGAUGGCUUUUCAGAGCCCUACCUGCAGUUCCAGGAUCCAACCAAGCAUUCUAGAAAGGUAAAUCCAUCCACUAAAUAUUUGGUCAUUUCUCUGGUCAUCCUUUCCUUUCUCUUUCUCCUCUCUGUCAUAGUGAUCUUCAUUAUACAUGUCUACCAAAAGAUUAAAUAUAGAGAAAAGUUCACAAUUCAAGAGCAUUUCUAUGAUGACUGUAAUUUCUCUAACAACCUGGUACAAGGACAAGGCAAUGGAUCCUUAUCUCGGCCUUGUCCAUAUGAAAUGUGUUCAGCCACUGGCACUGGUAAUAGUGAGUUUCGCUUUCUUAAGCGUUUUAUGCCCAACUUCCCUUUCCCUCAUGCCACUGGGGAGAUAAAAAUGGAGGCUGGCUCCAGUUUGCCCCCAAAUUCUGAUAGGAAUAAGUCUCAGAGAUUAGAGGGCCAUGACCAGGUAUCUGAUGACUAUAUGUAGCUCCUAUUUACAGGCUCAGUGAGAGAAGAGAAGCAAAAUUUUAUACUUGGUAUGCAAAGAUGUUACAUCCUCAUUAAAACAAAAACUGGUAGUAGAUUGCAGCUUUAGUAAAGAUAAGAGUACUUAGUUUGGUGAAAAUGGGAAACCUAGAGUGAGGCUAGGCUUACUCAAUACAAAGCAGUUAUCCUGAUCCCCAGAUCAUAUAUCUAUAACCCUUUCUCCAGUUGGAAUUCUGUUUAAAGAAAUGUCACCCUCUAUAAAUGCAUAUGUGGUAGGAACUUCUGCUUUUCCAUCUCUGUGCUAGCAAGUAAUGAAUAAGCCAUUAUUCACAUUUUCCUUAGAAGUUCAUUGGUCCUGGCCCAGGAAAUACUUAGUUCCAUAGAGAGAUCCUUUUAUUUGCCUCUAAAUUAUUUUCCAGUAGAAAGUUAUGCAUGCAUAGGGAAGAGAACUACCUUCCCUUUUUGAUAUAUUGGGAAGUGAUUAGGUUUGACAAGCAGAGAUAUAGUUUAUUAUUCAGGAAUCUCUAAAUUCUUGUCCCUGAUGAGUGAUUAUCUUUGAUCAAUACCUUGCCUGCAAUCAUUCAUAAUCAUAAUCAUGGAAAUGCCUGGUAAAUGGUGAUCUUCACAAAUAAUCAUGGUGGGAGGAAGGGUGGAGAAAGAAAAGGAUUUCACUUAUUUGCAAAUGUGAAUAAGGGCAGACAUAAGGAUAAAGAGAUUCAGUUUAGGAAUGUUCUCCAAAAUUAAAUUAGAUGUAGUUGUUUUUUUUUUUUUUUUUUUUUUUUUUGAGACGGAGUUUUUCUCUUGUUGCCCAGACUGGAGUGCAAUGGCACGAUCUCGGCUCACUGCAACCUCUGCCUCCUGGGUUCAAGCGAUUCUCCUGCCUCAGCCUCCUGAGUAGCUAGGAUUACAGGCAUGCGCCACCAUGCCCAGCUAAUUUUUUGGUAUUUUUAGUAGAGACGGGGUUUCACCAUGUUGGCCAGGCUGGUCAUGAACUUCUGACCUCAGGUGAUCCACCAGCCUCGGAAACCCAAAGCACUGGGAUUACAGGCAUAAGCCACCACGCCCAGCCAGAUUUGAUUUCUUGAUUGUUUGGAGCCAUAGGCAAGUCUCAAAUCUCCCUCUUUUAUAUCCAGAUGUCUAUCCUUGCAGUCCCAGAGAAAAUCUAUUUGAAAAAACGGAAAUGGAGGGUGGGUGAGGAAAAAAAUAAAGUAUGACGGCUGGGCACCGUGGCUCAUGGCUGUAAUCUCAGCACUCUGGGAGACGGAGGGAGGCAGAUCACCUGAGGUCAGGAGUUCGAGAUCACCCUGGCUAACAUGGCAAAACCCUAUCUCUACUAAAAAUACAAAAAUUAGUCAGUCGUGGUGGCACGCACCUGUAAUCCCAGGUACUCAAGAGGCUGAGGCUGGAGAAUCGCUUGAACCUGGGAGGUGGAGGUUGCAGUGAGCUGAGAUUGUGCCACUGCACUCCAGCCUGGGCAACAGAGUGAGACGCUGUCUCAAAAACAUAAAAAUAAAUACAUAAAUACAUAAAUACAUAAGGCCUGCUGUAGUUAAUAAGUGUUACAGAACACUCUAAACUAUUUUGUGCCAUUAAGUGUACACAACAUUUAUUGUAAACCAUUUUGUAGUUUGUAGAGCAAAUAUAAAAUAAAAAGACAUUAAAAUUAAAAAGUUCAUUAAUACUAAUUAAGUGGCAUUAAGGAAAGACACAUUUUCAGGUAGUACUAGAUUUGAUUGUAAGCCAUUUUCCUCUCUGAGUAUUCUGAAGUUAACACAUGCAAACUGAGAAAAAGUGGCAUUUUUAGUAAAUCAUUCAUAAAAUGAAAUGGAGUGGGGAGACAACUUAAGCUUCUCUUUGAUCACCACUGUUUGAUUUCAUAAGCUAUUCUGAGCCCUCUCAUUCUAAAAUAAGCCAAUGUUAAAACAUUAACAUAUUUCAGGGAUUCUCCCAACACUGCUAACUGUGCCUUGAAAGUCAAAAGUUUGCUUUAGAGAAGGGCAUGGUGGCUCAUACCUGUAGUCCCAGCUACUCAGGAGUCUGAAGGAGGAGGAUUGCUCAAGCCCAGGAGUUCAGGGGUGCAGUAAGCUAUGAUUGCACUUCUGCACUCCAGCCUGGGCAAAAGAGUGAAACCUCAUCUCAAAAAAAAAAAAAGUGUGCUUUAAUGAGGCUUUAAUUAUAUUCCUUAUUUUAUAAAAAUGUGUGUAAAUUCAGACUCACUAGAAUACAUCCUCUUGGUAUUUUAAGGGUAGAGCAUUAUCUUUUAAAAUACUUCUUAAAUAUACCAAAUCAUGUUUAUUGAUACAAACUUCAUUCUUGGACUUAAUGACUGAUACCUAAUGGCACCACCUGGCUGUUUACCUGUUGGCCAGGAAUACACUAAAAUUUAGUGCUGUUAUUUUUUAGAUGUUAGAGAUGCUUAGGGCAGAACUGGUGUAACCUAUGGCUGCCUUCAAUGUUAAAAUGUUAAAGAACAGAUGAAGCAAAUGCACUAUAUCAAUGAAUUGCUUUUAUUUUUAAUAUUAAAUAUUUUACAUACAUUGAGUUAUGAUUCCGAUUUAGAGUAAAGGUUUUCUUGCACAAAACAUAGAAUAAGUGUUCCAGUGUAUUUGUGUUCCAAUUGGUGAAGGCAUGCUGAAAUUUCUAUUUCCUUUAAAUGAAAAAGGAGAUAGAAUUUUUAUUUAUUUAUUUAUUUUUUGGAGACAAAGUCUUGCUCUGUCACCCAGGCUGGAGUACAGUGGCAUGAUCUCGGCUCACUGCAAACUCCGUCUCCUGGGUUCAAGUGAUCUUCCUGCCUCAGCCUCCUGAGUAGCUGGGACUACAGGUAUACAUUACCACGCCCAGCUAAAUUUUGUGUUUUUAGUAGAGACGGGGCUUCGCCAUGUUGGCAUUUCGCUAUGUUGGCCAGGCUGGUCUCGAGCUCCUGAUCUCAGGUGAUCCACCCGCCUUGGCCUCCCAAAGUGCUAGGAUUACAGCACCAUGCCCAGCCUAGAAUUAAUUUUUAUGGGUAAGCAAUAAUUAGUUAAUAAAACAUGCUUAAGUAAAAGCUACUGUAUUAACUGUGUUUCAUUACACUUAAUGAUGUGAACAUAAUCAAUGGAAACUGGCUUAAUGUCAAGGAUAGGAAAAGAAAAUGGUGUAGAUUCAUGAUUUUAAGACUUUGAUAUUCAAAUAGCAGUGAAAUUCAUGAAUACAUAUAUACACACAUACACAAUGGACAGAAGAUGUAGAUUUGUCAACUUUUUAUUUUUUCACAUUAAAUGAGAUAAAAUCUACCACUUCACGCCACCAUUAUUCCAUAAACGAAAUGGCAUUUUAAUAUAAAAAUGGUUAAGAUAGGCUGGGCAUGGUGGCUCACACCUGUAAUACCAGUACUUUGGGAGGCUGAGGCAGAUGGAUCACAAGGUCAAGAGAUGGAGACCAUCCUGGCCAACAUGGUGAAACCAUGUCUCUAUUAAAAAUACAAAAAUUAGCUGGGUGUGGUGGUAUGUGCCUGUAGUCCCAGCUACUUGGGAGGCUGAGGCAGGAGAAUUGCUUGCACCCAGGAGGUGGAGGUUGCAGUGAGCUGAGAUCAUGCCACUGCACUCCAGCCUGGCGACAAAGCAAGACUCUGUCUCAAAAAAAAAAAAAAAAAAGAAAAAAAGAAAAAAGAAAAAAAAAGGUAAGAUAACAAUCUCAUAAAAGAAACCAUCCUUUAAAUUUAAAAAAUGUAUCGAUUUAAUAAAAAAUUAUUUUGCCACCAUUUUUCUUAUUUUUGCCUUAGGUGAAAAUUUUGUCACUCUAAUUUUAUUCAGACUUCAAGUUCCCAAGAAAAUUCCAAUCCUACCUGAUAACUUAAAAUAAGAAUAUAUCAAUUCACUGAAUGUGAAGUAGGCCACUUGUUUUUGGAGAGAACUCUGUACACCAGCUGAGAUUAAGUCCAGGUCUCUAUCAGCAAAUUAAGACAAAGAAUGGAAAUAAUUAGGGCAAUUACUCUCUCCAAAGUGUCAAGUGAUAUUAUAACUAUUUCUAUGUAUUCAAAGCUAUAACCUAAGAACCUUGAAAAGUGUCUUGUACAAAAAGGCUUUUUAUUAGGAAAUAAUUCUAGACUCAUAAAAUUGCAAAAAUACUAUAGAUAGUUCCUGUAUAUCCUUCACCUAACUUCCCGGAAUGCUAACAUCUUAUAUAACCAUAGUAGUUAUCAAAAUUAAGAAAUUAACCUUGGUAUAAUUCUAUGAAGUAAACUACAGAUCUUAUUCAAAUUUAACAGUUUUCCCCCAAUGUCCUUUUUCUAUUCAAGGAUCCAAUCCAGGAUCCUGCAAAGCAUUUGUUAUGGCUCCUUAGUCUCUACCACCUGUGACAGUUCCUUACUCUUACCUUGUCUAUCAUGACUUGAGAUUUUUGAAGAGUACUAGCCAGUUAUUUGUAGAAUGCCCCUCAGUUUGGGAUUCUUUGUUUUCUCAUUAUUAAACUGAGGUAAUGCAUUAUUGGGAAAAAUACUGCAGAAAUGAUAUUGUAUCCUUUUCAGUGCAUCACGUCAGCAGGUAUGUGAUGCCAAUGUCACACUACUGGUGAUAUUAAUCUUUUUUCUUUUAUUGUGGUAAAGAACUUAUAAAAUGUACCAUGUUAGCCAUUUUUAAGUAUGUUAGCCAUUUUUAAGUAAUGUUAAGGUGAUGUUAAUUUUGAUCGCUUGGUUAACAUAAUGUCUGCCACGUUUCUCUACUAUAAAGUUACUUUUUUCUCUUUGUAAUUAAUAAACACUUGGGGGAUAUGCUUUGAAACUAUGCAAAUAUGAUGUUUCUGCUUAAACCAAUUUUAGUAUCCAUUGCUAGAUAUUUCCUGUGGCAAUUAAUAUUGUGGCAUUCUAAUGGUGAUUUUCUAUUUCUCUAUUUCCUUUUACAUUAAUUAAAAUUCUUCUGGAAGGAAAACUUGUUACUUUCCCCCCCACUUAUUUAGUUAGUUAUUUCUUUACAUAAGGAUACCUGGAUAUCUCCUCUAUUAUUUGGGUUACAAACUAAUCCUAUCAUUUACUUUGUUGUUCAGCAAACUCUUUUAUCUGAGAUGAAGAGCAGAUUUUUAAGACUGGAAUUAUCCAUAUAGAAUACAUUUUUAUCAAAAUUAGUAUUUCUUUGUAACUCUACAUGUUAGAUUAUUUUAAACAAUCAUAAAGUAACCCCAUUAAGGUUCAUGCAUAAAGUUUUAACUUUAAAUGAAAAUUAUACUAACAUAAUUUUAAAUUAGUCAUACAUUUUAAAAUAGAUAUAAACUGAAAAUUUUAAAAUUUGUUGUGCAGACAUGUUUAUAUAGUUUAAGCUAUAUAUACCUGAGAUACUAUUUAAAAAUAGACUUAUAUGCUGAAAUUAGACUUACAGAUAUACAAAAAAUGGAAUUGGUCUGUCUGAUAUUAUGUAAUUCUCCUAAAAAUAAAGAAUUUCUUUAUCAUG